GCUCGGGCGCGGGGCGUUCUUGGUGCGCCGGGCCGUGGUGAGUCCGGGCUCCCGUGGCCGCGUGCUGGGAGGAGACUGGAGCCCGGUUAGGAAGAAUGGAGUUGGCGACUCGCUACCAGAGCACUUCGCAGGCAUAGUUUGGAAGUCAUCAGGGCUGGUUCUUUUCCUUCCAGAUCCCUAAAGAAGUGGCUGACAUCUUUAACGCCCCCAGUGAUGAUGAAGAGUUUGUUGGCUUCCGAGAUGAUGUUCCCAUGGAAACCCUCUCGUCAGAGGAGAGCUGCGAUAGUUUUGACUCACUAGAGUCAGGGAAACAGCAGGAUGUGCGCUUUCAUUCCAAAUACUUCACAGAAGAGCUAAGAAGAAUUUUUAUAGAGGACACUGACUCAGAGACUGAGGAUUUUGCAGGAUUUACGCAGAGUGAUCUGAAUGGAAAGACUAACCCAGAAGUAAUGGUCGUGGAGUCAGAUUUGAGUGAUGAUGGCAAAGCAUCUUUGGUGAGCGAGGAAGAGGAAGAUGAAGAAGAAGAUAAGGCUACCCCUAGAAGAAGCAGGUCUAGAAGAAGUAGUAUUGGUCUUCGAGUAGCCUUUCAGUUCCCCACCAAGAAGCUGGCCAACAAACCAGAUAAAAACAGUUCUUCCGAGCAGUUGUUUUCUAGCGCACGCUUACAGAAUGAGAAAAAAACAAUUCUUGAAAGAAAGAAAGACUGUAGACAGGUGAUACAAAGGGAAGAUUCUACCUCUGAGUCUGAGGAUGACUCUCGGGAUGAGAGCCAGGAGAGUUCAGAUGCUUUGCUGAAAAGGACCAUGAACAUCAAGGAGAACAAAGCCAUGCUUGCCCAGUUAUUGGCGGAAUUGAACUCGAUGCCAGAUUUCUUCCCAGUACGAACCCCAACCUCAGCUUCUAGGAAGAAGACAGUGAGGCGGGCCUUCUCGGAGGGACAGAUCACGCGGCGUAUGAACCCAACCCGGAGUGCGCGGCCUCCUGAGAAGUUUGCUCUAGAGAACUUCACUGUCUCAGCCGCUAAAUUUGCGGAAGAGUUUUACAGCUUCCGAAGAAGGAAGACAAUUGGGGGGAAAUGCCGGGAGUACAGACGACGUCACCGUAUAUCUUCUUUUCGGCCAGUGGAGGAUAUCACCGAAGAGGACUUAGAAAAUGUUGCCAUAACUGUUCGAGAUAAAAUCUAUGAUAAAGUUCUGGGUAACACGUGCCAUCAGUGUCGACAAAAGACCAUCGACACCAAGACAGUGUGUCGGAACCAGGGUUGCUGUGGUGUGCGAGGACAGUUCUGUGGACCAUGCCUGCGGAACCGCUAUGGGGAGGAUGUCAGAUCGGCAUUGCUGGACCCGGAUUGGGUGUGUCCCCCCUGUCGUGGGAUCUGCAAUUGCAGCUACUGUCGGAAGCGUGACGGCCGCUGUGCCACAGGAAUCCUCAUUCAUCUGGCCAAGUUUUAUGGUUAUGACAAUGUUAAGGAAUAUCUGGAGAGCUUACAAAAGGAGCUGGUAGAAGACAAUUAAGAGGAAAACAAACAGAACCAGCCACCUCACCAUAGAGUACUCCAACAAGACAUGCAUACCAUUGGUGCCUAAGAAAGAUUUUUUUACAGUUGUGUUUUUAUACAGAAAUUCUUUGUAGAAAUUACUAUUUUUUGUUAAAGAUUGUUUAUAUGCUUACAAAGAUUUCUCAGGAAGACAGCAGAGCAGAGGAAUCUAUAUAGAUGUAUGCACAGACCUGUCUGUAUGCUGAACUUUGUUAAAAAUAUCUGCCAGUUAUUAAAAAGCACAGUUUAAAUGGGGUGGGGUUAAAGUUCAGGUAAGUAAGUUAGAGAGAAAACAUUGUAUGAUCAGCUCCUGCACUUGAUCUAUCUAUCUUUGGCUUCCCAAACAGUAACUCACUCCAGGCCAAGUGUGCCUUAGCACGAGUGACCACAGUUUAAUAGACCACACACAUCGUUUAACCUGCUCUUGGUCAUUGGAAAUUUACACUGAACAAAGUGCAAUUAACUGUAGAACAGUUUUAUUUUUAUUAAAACUUGACUGAACAAAAGGGGACCAUCAACAUUGUAGACACUGGACACUGGAGGCCUUACAGAGUGCUAGCCUCUUCCUUCAGGACUCACCUGGGGCCUGCUGCUUUUAUAUUUUGAAAGAGUUUAAGGGCUAAUAAUUUAAUUUGUUGUUUGUUAAAAAUUAAAAUCUCCGUUCUUUCCGGCUGCAUUGCUUUUGCAUGUUCACAUAUGAUGUACUUUUAUGAUGUACUUUUUUUUUUUUGAGAUGGAGUCUUGUUCUGUUGCCCAGGAGGGAGUGCAGUGGUGCAACCUCGGCUCACUGCAACCUUUGCCUCCUAGGUUCAAGUGAUUCUCCUACCUCCUGAGUAACUGGGAUUACAGUCGUGUGCCACCACGCUCAGCCCUGAGUUAGUUUCUAGUAUUUUUUUCUGACUUUCACUCUAAGGAUAGCGUUGAAAAAAGAAUGCACGUGUGAGUUACUAAAAAGUUAGAAUAAUGUGCAUGGGAACAGUGCAGCAACAUGCUAGAAAAUCCUCACUGCACUCCAGCAGAGGCUAGAGGAAUGCCAGUGUUACCUUACGCUUCUAGAAGCAGAGCCACUCCAGCCAGAACCCAUUUUGCAGUCUUCUCUUCGCUCUUCAGCCUGAAGGUCCAGAUGUAGCUGGGGCCUCUCAGUUUGGUUCUAUACACAGGGCACUCGUAGGUCUGUUUGGUUUCUUGUCUGUCCACGGGGGUGGCUUUUGCAAAGAUGACCGGCAUAGGGCAUGCCAGCUCCUUGAGACGGGCUUCAACAAUGGUUCCUGCUUGGGUGUCCCAGCGGGCGCCUAUGGCAAAAACACAGCGGUUGCAAUUGUGUGGCAGCUUGCUACUAAUGAUAAUGAUCAAGUAAGUUGUUUGAUGCAAUAAACAUUCAACAUUCUGGUUUUGUCAUA